GGUGGCCGAAGUGGGACGCGCCGAGCCGGAGGCUGCAGGAUGAUGCGGUUCAUGCUAUUAUUCAGCCGGCAGGGAAAACUGCGGCUGCAAAAAUGGUACCUGGCCACUUCGGACAAGGAACGGAAGAAGAUGGUGCGCGAGCUCAUGCAGGUUGUCCUGGCUCGAAAGCCCAAGAUGUGCAGCUUCCUGGAGUGGAGGGACCUCAAAGUUGUCUAUAAGAGAUAUGCCAGCCUCUACUUCUGCUGCGCCAUCGAGGGCCAAGACAAUGAGCUCAUCACACUGGAGCUGAUCCACCGAUACGUGGAGCUCUUAGACAAAUACUUUGGCAGUGUGUGCGAGCUGGACAUCAUCUUCAACUUUGAGAAGGCCUACUUCAUCCUGGAUGAGUUUUUGAUGGGGGGGGAUGUCCAGGACACCUCCAAGAAGAGUGUGCUGAAAGCCAUCGAGCAGGCUGACCUACUGCAAGAGGAGGAUGAGUCGCCACGGAGUGUGCUGGAGGAGAUGGGUUUGGCAUAGCCCCUGCUGGGCCGGGGUGUGGCGAUGGGGUCCUGGCAGCGUGGCGGGAACGGCUGCUUCUCCUCUGCCCAGGGCCCUGUUCUUGGUGGGACUCGGCUGCCCCUCCUCUGCUGCCUCACCUUUCGGAGUGAGCUGUGGGCUCAGGCCCUUCAAACAUUCCCUCCCUCCACCCCCUACCUCCACUUUCCCCUUUUCCCACUGAAGGUUUUAGAAGCUAGGAGGCAGGAAAAUGUGACCCAGAUGGGGGUGCUAUUUGGCUUUUAUUCCCUGCCUUUGCAGAACUGAUGUCACCCCAGAUGUCCUUCCCUCCCUAAUAACUGUAAAUAUAUAAAUAUGUCAGGUUAAAGGGAAAAGGUGUUCAGGGCACUUCUUGUCCUCUCUGUCCCAUAACCUACCUCCACCCUCCCCCUAGCCAGCCAGGCAGCUUCUCUGCCUGGGAGGGGAGCCUGGACCCCCCUCUUUCUCCUUGGCUGCAGUGGGGCCUUUAUCCAGUGCCAGGGAGGAACAACAUAGUUAAUUUUUUUCUAACCUUGCCACUUUGAGGGAAGGAAGGGUUGGGGGAAGGGCAAGCUUUAUGGGACCCUGGUCCUGGCCCUGGCCUUUCACUCCAGUUCUGGGUGAGGCAGGAGCUGGGAGGGGUGGGGAGGGGGAGGGGGAAGUGUCUGCCUUUAUGUCCUUUCUUCUGAAAUAAAAGUAAAAGCAUUUCUGGA